AGUUACCGGCUAGUAAACAACAGCUGCGCGCGCACCCGCAUCAGCUGGCGCCGGGAUACUGCACCUGCGACCUCCUUCUCCCUCACCCUGCUGCCCAGUCAGGCCAGCCUGCGUGGCCGUCUCCUCCUCUACUGGGACCCUGAGGAAGAACGACGAGGGGGUGACCUGCGCCGGGGCGGGGGUAGGGGAGAACGCGCCUCCGGCAAAGGGGGUGGCUCGUCCUGUCACACGCAGGAGAAACCUAGCGAGCGGACCGUGGCUCAGUGGACUAGCUACGACUUGCCACGACUCUGAGCUGCAGUCCGAGGUGUCUUGAUCCGCUAACCUCCUCCCAGACCCCGAGGACCUUUCUGCUAGGAGAAGAGCGGGCGCGCCACCCCCACCGACCUCUCGGAGACAGGAAUCCGCUCUGCCCCUGCAUCCUCCUCUGCUCACCCUUCUCUCAGUAGUUCAAAAGUAGCUAGCGUAAGAGGAAGAUUUUGCGAGGUUCCCCCCACUUUUUUUGUUCUUAAAAAGAACAAAAUGCAUCCUCCAGAAACCACCACCAAGAUGGCUUCAGUUCGGUUCAUGGUGACACCGACAAAGAUCGAUGACAUUCCAGGUUUGUCAGACACCAGUCCGGACCUCAGCUCUCGAUCUAGUUCCCGAGUAAGAUUUAGCUCCCGGGAAAGCGUGCCUGAAACAAGCCGGAGUGAGCCUAUGAGUGAGAUGUCUGGGGCCACCACUUCGCUGGCAACUGUUGCACUGGAUCCACCCAGUGACCGGACUUCUCACCCCCAGGAUGUCAUCGAGGACCUGAGUCAGAACUCCAUCACAGGGGAACACAGCCAACUGUUAUAAUUUGACAAGAAUCUCUUUUUUUUUUUGAGACAGUGUCUCGCUCUGUCACCAGGCUGGAGUGCAGUGGUGCGAUCUCCACUCACUGCAAGCUCCGCCUCCCAGGUUCAUGCCAUUCUCCUGCCUCAGCCUCCCAAGUAGCUGGGACUACAGGCGCCCGCCACCACACCCUGUGCUCCUGCAAGAAACAUAAUAGUGUCUGGGCGCAGUGGCUCACACCUGUAAUCCCAGCAGUUUGGGAGGCUGAGGUGGGUGGAUCACCUGAGGUCAGGAGUUCAAGACCAGCCUGGCCAACAUGGCAAAACCCCAUGUCUACUAAAAAUACAAAAAAUUAGCCAGGCAUGGUGGCAGGCGCCUAUAAUUCCAGCUACUCGGGAGGCUGAGGUAGGAGAAUUGCUUGAACCCUGGAGGCGGAGGUCGCAGUCUGCUGAGAUUGUGCCACUGCACUGCAGACUGGGCAACAGAGCAAGACUCCGUCUCAAAAAAAAA